GAGGAGACCCUAAGAUGGCGGCGAGGGGGACGGUGAAGGUUGCCUCCCGCCCGUCCGGGCUCUGAUCCUCCGUCUCCCCGUCCCCCGGCGGCCGGCCCAUGGCCUGGCGGAGGCCCGAACCAUGGACCUCCGCACCGCCGUGUACAACGCCGCCCGUGAUGGCAAGCUGCAGCUGCUCCAGAAGCUGCUCAGCGGCCGGAGCCGGGAGGAACUGGACGAGCUGACGGGCGAGGUGGCCGGCGGGGGAACGCCGCUACUCAUCGCCGCCCGCUACGGCCACCUGGACGUGGUGGAGUACCUGGUGGACCGGUGCGGCGCGAGCGUGGAGGCCGGUGGCUCGGUGCACUUCGAUGGCGAGACCAUCGAGGGCGCGCCGCCGCUGUGGGCCGCCUCCGCAGCCGGCCACCUGGACGUGGUGCGGAGCCUGCUGCGCCGCGGGGCCUCGGUGAACCGCACCACGCGCACCAACUCCACGCCUCUCCGCGCCGCCUGCUUCGACGGCCACCUGGAGGUGGUGCGCUACCUGGUCGGCGAGCACCAGGCCGACCUGGAGGUGGCCAACCGGCACGGCCACACGUGCCUCAUGAUCUCGUGCUACAAGGGCCACCGUGAGAUCGCCCGCUACCUGCUGGAGCAGGGCGCCCAGGUGAACCGGCGCAGCGCCAAGGGCAACACGGCCCUGCAUGACUGCGCCGAGUCCGGCAGCCUGGAGAUCCUGCAGCUGCUGCUGGGGUGCAAGGCCCGCAUGGAACGUGACGGCUACGGCAUGACCCCGCUGCUCGCGGCCAGCGUGACGGGCCACACCAACAUCGUGGAGUACCUCAUCCAGGAGCAGCCCGGCCAGGAGCAGGUCGCAGGGGGAGAGGCUCAGCCUGGGCUGCCCCAAGAAGACCCCUCCACCAGCCAGGGGUGUGCGCAGCCUCAGGGGGCUCCGUGCUGCAGCUCCUCCCCAGAGGAACCACUGAACGGGGAAUCUUACGAAAGCUGCUGUCCCACCAGCCGGGAAGCUGCCGUGGAAGCCUUGGAAUUGCUGGGAGCUACGUAUGUGGAUAAGAAACGAGAUCUGCUUGGGGCCCUUAAACACUGGAGGCGGGCCAUGGAGCUGCGUCACCAGGGGGGCGAGUACCUGCCCAAACCGGAGCCCCCACAGCUGGUCCUGGCCUAUGACUAUUCCAGGGAGGUCAACACCACCGAGGAGCUGGAGGCGCUGAUCACCGACCCGGAUGAGAUGCGCAUGCAGGCCCUGUUGAUCCGGGAGCGCAUCCUCGGUCCCUCGCACCCGGACACUUCCUAUUACAUCCGUUACAGGGGUGCCGUGUACGCCGACUCGGGCAAUUUCGAGCGCUGCAUCCGCUUGUGGAAGUACGCCCUGGACAUGCAACAGAGCAACCUGGAGCCUCUGAGCCCCAUGACCGCCAGCAGCUUCCUCUCCUUCGCGGAACUCUUCUCCUACGUGCUUCAGGACCGGGCCGCCAAAGGCAGCCUGGGCACCCAGAUCGGCUUUGCAGACCUCAUGGGGGUUCUCACCAAAGGGGUCCGGGAAGUGGAACGGGCCCUGCAGCUGCCCAGGGAGCCCGGAGACUCAGCCCAGUUCACCAAGGCGCUGGCCAUCAUCCUCCACCUGCUCUACCUGCUGGAGAAAGUGGAGUGCACCCCCAGCCAGGAGCACCUGAAGCACCAGACCGUCUACCGCCUGCUCAAGUGCGCGCCCAGGGGCAAGAACGGCUUCACCCCUCUGCACAUGGCUGUGGACAAGGACACCACAAACGUGGGCCGCUAUCCCGUGGGCAGAUUCCCCUCCCUGCACGUGGUCAAAGUGCUGCUCGACUGCGGGGCCGACCCGGACAGCAGGGAUUUUGACAACAACACCCCGCUACACAUAGCAGCCCAGAACAACUGCCCGGCCAUCAUGAAUGCCCUGAUCGAAGCAGGGGCCCACAUGGACGCCACCAAUGCCUUCAAGAAGACGGCCUACGAGCUGCUGGACGAGAAGCUGCUGGCCAGGGGUACCAUGCAGCCCUUCAACUACGUGACCCUGCAGUGCCUUGCGGCCCGGGCCCUGGAUAAGAACAAGAUCCCUUACAAGGGCUUCAUCCCGGAAGAUCUGGAGGCGUUCAUCGAACUGCACUGACCUGCCCAGAACGCCUGCACCCUCACCUCUCCCCUCUCCUGCUGAGAUGGGGGAAAUCCGGCUGCGGCAUAGCAGAUGCUCGUUCUUGCCUCCUUCAGGCACCAAUCAGGAGAAGGGUUCUGCCUCCCAUCCCCUCUACCUGCAGACAGGGUCGGAGGUGUUAGCGAGCCUUUGGUGCUAGAAGCCUGCGGGGUCAUGUGCUAAGAGGACAGUCUUUCUCCGGGAGCCCGCUCACUCAUUCUGAGUUAGGAAAAGACACAAGACCUUCCCCACAUCCUGUCUGCCUGGGUUAGGGAGGCCUUUGCCUUGUUACCUAGAGGCGGAGGGACUGAAGCCAUUGCGUUCCUUCCCUGCUAGAAACACAGGAAGAAGUUGAGGACUGUCUGCCUUCCCUCGUCCCUUUACCUGGCCAGAUAACUCCAGCCGCUGAAUACAGUGUUAGGACUGGGGGCUCCUGAGAUGAGAGUUUGAGAUUCAGGGAAUGAGACCACCUCUCAUUUCUUCCAGCAUGAUCGCGCCCUGCUCCCGUGCCACCGUAGUCCCUGGCAGACAGGCAGGGCUCUGCCCAGGGCAGCCUGCCACUUGCAUAGCUUUCGGUUGGUUUGGUGUUCUGUUUAUUUAAUAAGUGGGCAGGUUGCAAGCGUUGCACAGAAAUUCUGAGAUUUUACUGCCUUUUUUUUUUUUUUUAAGAAAGUUGUUUGUUGGACUCCAUAAGUGAAUUUCAAGCAGUGAGGAUUUUGUGGUGCCUGAGAUGGCCGAGGGCACAGGGAGUGAGCUGUAUGUGUGAGGAAUUUGGUGAGCGAGAUAAAAGUCCACGGUGUCAACCCCUAAAACAUGGGUGACCGUACAUUUUUAUACAUCUCCACUCUACGGCCUUUUACAGGCUUUCCGAUUUUACAGGCCUUUCCAAGUUUCCAUUCUCCUUAGAGAGAGAACUGUGCUUCCAAACAGAAAUCAGGAGUGACCACAAAGCCUGAAAACACUUUGCCACCCAGCAAAGAACUGGCACAAUUGGUUUGGGUCUGCAUUGCCAUAGUGCCCGAGUUAAAACUGCAGGCCACUCUGCCUUGCAGUGGCCUCUGAUUUCAUUGUGGGUGCAUCCACAGGUGGCCCGAGCUGUUCUUUCAGCUGCUCCAAGGAUUGAGACCCAAGUCAUCAUGAAAAAGGCCCAAGUACAGUCUUAAUGCGAUAAAUCCACUAGCUAAGACGUCGAGUGCCAAGACCAGCCUUCCAGCCGAGGUUUGGACAAAGUCUCAGGUUCCCGUGACUCAGGGUAAGGUGCUGGGGCUGCCAGAGGACCUGCCCCAGCAAGAUUUUUGUCAAGAGCGAGACUCCAUCAGCCCAGGCAGACGGGAGCAGGUUCUUGGCCAGCGUAGACAGCAGCAAACAGCAGCAGGGAAGCCAUUCUCACUGCAUCCUCCCUGCAGUAGCCACGGCCAGGCCCUUAGGAGGAGCAGUGACCGGGGGUGUCCAGAAAUAUCCUGUCCCUGGAUGGAAACUAGGUCUCGUUUGGAUUUUUUUUUUUUUUUGCCGUGUUAGGAAAUUAUUUAUUAAUUUACAAGACAGGUUUUAACUCAGCCGAGGUGGGAAAUGGUGUCCCUGUCCCUCCCAAAGCACAGAGCACAGAAAUGAGGCCGUUUACAUGGCGAGUCUCCGUGCUGGUGUUUAAGUCAUUAAAAAGAUACUCAAAGAGAAUGGCCUGCCUGAUGCGUCCUUGGCGUGGGUUAACUGGGGAAGUCGGAGGUGGGUGAGUCAGUCCAUGGCAUUGGUGUGAGUGAACAGAGAGCCCUAGGGCCACCUCCCCUAGCCAGAGGGGUUUCUGUGUUACAUACUGGGGCUUUUUUUUUUUUUUUGAGACAGAGUCUCACCCUGUCCCCCAGGCUGGAGUGCAAUGGCGCGAUCUCAGCUCACUGCAACCUCUGCCUCCUGGGUUCAAACAAUUCUGCUUCAGCCUCCUGAGUAGCUGAGAUUACAGGCACCUGCCACUAUGCCCAGCUAAUUUUUGUAUUUUCUGUAGAGGCAGGUUUUGCCAUGUUGGCCAGGCUGGUCUCAAACUCCUGAACUCAAGCGAUCCUCCCACCUCAGCCUCCCAAAGUGCUGGAAUUACAAGCAUGAACCACUGCACCUGGCCUCUAUGUUACAUACUGGGGCUUUGUGUAAAAUUUCAUUUGAAAAACAGUAUGUUGCUCUUUGAAAAAAAGCCUGGGCAACAUAGUGAGAGCCUGUCUUUACAAAAAUAAAAAAUAGGCUGGGUACGGUGGCUCACAUCUGUAAUCUCAGCACCUUGGGAAGCCUGGGCAACAUAGUAAGACCUCUGUCUCUACAUUUUUUUUUUUUUUUUUUUUGAGAUGGAGUCUUGCUCUGUCACCCAGGCUGGAGUGCAGUGACGCCAUCUCGGCUCACUGCAACCGCUGCCUCCCGGGUUCAAGUGAUUCUCCUGCCUCAGCCUCCUGAGCAUCUGGGACUACAGGCAUACACCACCAUGCCUGGCUAAUUGUGUAUUUUUAGCAGAGACGGGGUUUCACCAUAUUGGCCAUGCUGGUCUCAAACUCCUGACCUUGUGAUCCACUCGCCUCGGCCUCCUAAAGUGCUGGGAUUAUAGGUGUGAGCCACCACGCCUGGCCCUUUUUUGUUUUCCUUUAUCUGCCAUCUCAUCUCACCUCCUUGUGUAAACUUGUUCCAUUCUAAAAUUCUGGUUUUCUCCAUAUCAGAACAGUCAAACCCCCACCAGAAAGCACCACCCCGUUAGCUGGGUCCAUGGGAUUUUGCUGAGCCCCUGCCAUGUGCCAGGCAGGUUUCAGGCCCCCUUGGGGAUAAGGAUUGAGCUGUCGAUAUGAACGUCCGGUUAAUCCCUGUGCGCCCGCCUCACGUGGCAGUGGGGAGAGGCCCUGCUGUGGGGCACCGCAUGCUGCUUCCAUGGUGCAUUGGGUUGGAGGGCUCUUCUCCCGAGGGUGGGUGUCUCCCAUCUCUUGCCUUCACACACCUGCUGUCUUGUUUCAUUUGGGACUGGACAGUCCCACAGGUGACAGCUGUUGGGCUGUUGUAUGCCUGUUUGGUGUUGCAUCAAAGGAGUGGGUUUGAAUCAGCAGGUGCUCUCAAAGCUGUCUCCUGGGAGACACAGUACUAGUGAGCAUUUAUUGAGCACCUACUGUAUGCCAGGCACCAUUUUCUGUGGUUAAAUGCACUGCCUGUUUACACAACAGCCCUCUAAAGGAGGAAAAACAUAUCAGAGUCCCAUGGAUGGAAGAAAAAUAAUGAAGUAGGAAAAACGGCCCUCUUAAGAUGAAGGUCAUCUUUUUUUUUUUUUUUUUUUUUUUUUGAGACGGAGUCUCUGUCGCUCAGGCUGGAGUGCAGUGGUGUGAUCUCGGCUCACUGCAAGCUCAGCCUCCCGGGUUCACACCAUUCUCCUGCCUCAGCCUCCCGAGUAGCUGGGACUACAGGCACCUGCCACCAUGCCCGGCUAAUUUUUUGUAUUUUUAGUAGAGAUGGGGUUUCACCGUGUUAGGAUAGUCUUGAUCUCCUGACCUCAUGAUCCGCCCACCUCGGCCUCCCAAAGUGCUGGGAUUACAGGCAUGAGCCACCGCACCCGACCAGAUGAAGGCCAUCUUAAAGCUCAACCAGUUUCAGGUGAGGGCUGAUCCAGCAGAUCCCAAUUAUUCCUAAAGACCUGGUUGAUAGCUCCCUUGAGACUGGGGUGGGGUGGGUGUCCCAAGAUGACCGCCAGCAGAAAAGAGAGCAUCUUUCUCCCAGUCAAAAGCCAAAGUAGGACCUAUCUAAAGUAAGUCCUGGCCGGGCACGGUGGCUCACACCUGUAAUCCCAGCACCUUGGGAGGCUGAGGCUGGAGGAUCGCUUGAGCCUGGGAGUUUGAGACCAUCAUGGGCAGCAAAGUGAGAUCCUGUCUCUACAAAAAAAAAAAAAAAAAAAAAUUAGCCAUGUGUAGUGAUAUGUAGUCCCAGCUGCUACUGGGGAGGCUGAAGCAGGAGGAUUGAUUGAGCCCAGGAGUUUGAGGCUGCAGUGAGCCUUAAUGGCACCAUCACACUCCAGCCUGGGCAACAGAGUGAGACCCUGUUUCAAAAAAACAAAGCAGGGCCGGGCGCAGGGGCUCACGCCAGUAAUCCCAGCACUUUGGGAGGCCAAGGCGGGCGGAUCACGAGGUCAGGAGAUCGAGACCAUCCUGGCUAACACGGUGAAACCCCGUCUCUACUAAAAAUACAAAAAUUAGCCGGGUGUGGUGGCAGGUGCCUGUAGUCCCAGCUACUCCGGAGUCUGAGGCAGGAGAAUGGCGUGAACCCGGGAGGCGGAGCUUGCAGUGAGCCGAGAUCGCACCACUGCACUCCAGCCUGGGCGACAGAGCGAGACUCCGUCUCAAAAAACAAACAAACAAACAAACAAAACAAAGCAGGUCCGGUAUGGCAGGCGGGGGAACUGAGGCUACUAAGAGACAUUAAGAUGCUUAAGGACAGCCGGGCGCGGUGGCAGACGCCUGUAAUCCCAGCACUUUGGGAGGCUGAGGCGGGCGGAUCACGAGGUCAGGAGACCAAGACCAUCCUGGCUAACACGGUGAAACCCCGUCUCUCUACUAAAAGCACAAAAAAUUAGCCAGGCAUGGUGGUGGGCGCUUGUAGUCCCAGCUACUCGGGAGGCUGAGGCAGGAGAAUGGUGUGAACUCAGGAGGCGGAGCUUGCAGUGAGCCGAGAUCGCACCACUGCACUCCAGCCUGGGCGACAGAGCACAAGACUCCAUCUCAAAAAAAAAAAAAAGAAAGAAAAAUGCCUAAGGACACAGCGCAUGAAGGAAGGGUCGAGAUUGGAACCCAGGACCGUCAGAGUUCAUACCUUGUGCUGAUUCUCCAUCCGGGACGCCAGACACAUGGAUCCCUUUCCCCUGCUUUCUGGUGUUGUUUUGGCACAAGCUCUCCCAUCCCUGGGGCAGGUGGCCAUCCUGCCUCCGCAUCCUGAGCGUCUGUUUCCCUCGGGGAUCUGCCAGACUCAGCCCCCUAACCCCAAGAAAAUCACUCACAAAAAUCAUCUGAGCUAAAUGCUUGCUUUGAAAGCUCAGACCUGGGGAUUGUAACUUUAGCCUCAUACCUUCUAAUGAAGGCCAUCUUAAAGCUCUACCAGUUUCAGCUGAGGGCCGAUCCAGCAGAUCCCAGUUGUUCCUAAAGACCUGGUUGCUAGCUCCUCUGAGACUGGGGUGGGGUGGGUGUCCCAAGGUGAUGACCAGGAGAAAAGAGAGCGUCUUCCUCCCAGUCACAUCCCAAGAUUCGUGACCGAGCGCGGUGGCUCACGCCUGUAAUUCCAGCACUUUGGGAGACCGAGGCAGGUGGAUCACGAGGUCAGGAGUUCGAGACCAGCCUGGUCAACAUGGUGAAACCCUAUCUAUUCUAAAAAUACAAAAAAUUAGCCAGGCACGGUGGCAGGCACCUGUAAUCCCAGCUACUUGGGAGGCUGAGGAAGGAGAAUCGCUUGAACCCGGGAGAUGGAGGUUGCAGUGAGCCGAGAUUGCACCACUGCACUCCAGCCUGGGCAACAGAGCAAGACUCUGUCUCAAAACAAAACAAAACAAACAAACAAACAAACAAACAAAAAACUAAAAACAUCAAGAUACGCUCUGAUUGGACCAGCCUGGGUCCCAUGUUCUUCCAUGACCCAAUCCUAGUAGCCCAGGAGUGGGAUGUGCCAAUUGGCUUGGCCUGAGGAGGGCCCCCAGAGGGUCUGUAAUCCAUGUGUAACUGGAGUUGCUGUAAAAUGGGGCCAUCUGGCUGGGUGCGGUGGCUCACGCCUGUAAUCCCAACACUUUGGGAGGCCGAGGCGGGCGGAUCACGAGGUCAGGAGAUCAAGACCAUCCUGGCUAACACGGUGAAACCCCGUCUCUACUAAAAAUACAAAAAAUUAGCCGGGCGUCGUGGCAGGCGCCUGUAGUCCCAGUUACUCGGGAGGCUGAGGCAGGAGAGUGGCGUGAACCCGGGAGGCGGAGUUACAGUGAGCCGAGAUCGCGCCACUGCACUCCAGCCUGGGUGACAUAGCAAGACUCUGUCUCAAAAAAAAAAAAAAAAAAAAAAAAAAAAAUGGGGCCAUCAAUGCCAUGGAGGGUAGCAAAAAAUGUUCACAAUAGUAAAAUGACUACCUGCCGUUGAUCAGUGAAGAAAAAAGCUCAGAGAGCUCAAGUGGAGUACCUAAGGCCACACAGCCAAGAGGGAGAGCCAAGUCGUUUGUGGUUAAAUGUCCUGCCUGUUUACACAGCAGCCCUCUAAAGGCGGAAAAACAUGUCAGAGUCCCAUGGACGGGAGAAAAAUAAGAAUAAUAAUAAAGUAGGAAAAACAGCCCUCUUAAGAGGAAGGCCAUCUUAAAGCUCUACCAGCUUCAGGUGAGGGCUGAUCCAGCAGAUCCCAGAGAAACAGGCUCACAGAGAGGGGAGGGGGCUUGUCUAAGCUUACCCAGCCCGGAAGCAUCGGGGUCAAAGCUUAACCCCCUGCUGGAAGGUGUCGAGAGCCAGGCAGCCAAGCCUGACCUGGGAGAUGGGGAAGUGGGGGCCCCCCCAAGCUCGCCGACUGCCCUUCCCAGCCUGCUGCCAGUCUGAUUCCACAGAACUGAAGUCGGGACCUGGAGUUCUGCUCAUUCGCUCAUCUACUCAGUGACUUUCUUAGACCCUCCCCAGCACUUUGAGGGUGUCAGUCACUGCUGCGUCCUCAGCACCCACGCCAGGGUCUGUCCCACGCCAGGUGGCCUGUAAAUAUGGGCUGAGCAAGCGAACAGUGAACGAGUUGGGAAUUCACAUCCUCCUCUGACUACUUGGGGCAGCAGCAGGGGACACAAGCAGGCCCCUAUGGCUUUGCCAGACCCCGGGUGCCGCCGCCCCCAUGGAAUUGCAGGACUGUUAUCUGAGCAACGUCGACGGGGGAGAACACCCCUGCCCGAGGUUAAAGAUAGCACCGCUCGAAUCACAUCACAGGCCGAAAAGGCCAGAUGACCCACCAGGGACAUUGAAUCCGUGUCCCGAGAGGGGUGGGGCGGGGGUGUGGAUUCCUGCGGGGAGCUUCGGGACUGGAAAAAACAGAGGGUGCUCUGACCGAGUGUUUACCAAAACAUGUAUUAGGCAAGACCCGGGCCGAAUGUGGGUGGCACCGCCCCUGUGCUGGGCCAGGAGAAUGUGCCCGCACCGGUCCCAGAUCCUGUUUCCCCAGUGGGUUGUACAAGACACCUUGAACUUCUGCAUGAACUGGGACAUUCAGAAUUCCCUGGAGCAACCCCCUCCCUCCACCCUGUGCCUUGAUAUCUCCUAUUAAAGCUUGUGUUUGAAUGUCUGUUAAUAGACAUGAUUUAAUUAUUGAUAUUAAUUCAAAUGUAUUAAUUUGAAUUAUUAACUUAUUAAUCAUUUGAUGUCGAUUAAAGCAAUGAUCUUGAUCCAA